AGUCAAGUGACGCGAAGCGGCCGGCCUGGGCGCCGACUGCAGAGCCGGGAGGCUGGUGGUCAUGCCGGGGUUCCUGGUUCGCAUCCUCCCUCUGUUGCUGGUUCUGCUGCUUCUGGGCCCUACGCGCGGCUUGCGCGUAAGUCUGCGGGACCCGGGUACGGGGAGGCAUUGCUAGGGGACAGGCUGGCGGGGAACCGGGCUGGGGUCGCAGCCACCCGCGGUCCCGCAGGGCGGGGAGCCUGAGCCCCGAAGUGCCCCCCAGCAGGCUCGCGGCCGGCGGAACGCAGGCAGUGGACCGGCCUUCCCGUCGGGGGCGGGCCGGGCGGGGCGCGCGUCCUUCCAGGCAGCUCGGUCGCUUGUGCGUUCCGCUCCGGCCGCCCUUUGCGCUUGGAUCCACUUCCCCAUCUGUAACGAGGUGUUGAGACGAGGCGGAGUUGACCUGGAAACCUCUCCUUGGCCACUGUCCUUUCUAAGGAACUCAUUUCCAGAGUCCACCAGCACAGAACUGGUGGGGGAGCCUACUAGGAGCAGAGAAAAUGGCCAUCUUCAGGCAGCUGUCCCUAGGCGCGAAGGCCACCCUGGCUGCUGUCACUGUCUUCGUGUCCAUGAUCGCCUCCCGCUCGUAUCUGGCAGAGAGCCUUGAGCUCAGGGCCUGGCGUUGGCUGCUUCGCUUGCAGCUUGCCCUGUUUGUCAACUCGCUCUUGCUCAUUGGCUCCCUCUACAUUUGGCGCAGCACAGUGAGCAACCUCUGCCACUCCCCAGCUGCAGAGUCAACCUGUUUUCAGCUUUGGAAGGUGGUGGUUCUGGCAUUUCUGGCCCUGGCCCAUUCCAGUUUCUUUACCAUGUUCUUUUUAGUGGCCGAAGAGCCCUAUCUCUUUUCCUUGGCGGCCUACUCCUGCCUGGGUGCUUACAUCAUCAUGCUCUUCUUCCUCUUCAUCCUCAGCGGCAUGGAGCAGGCCUACCAGCUCUUGGCCUGGCGCAGUGGUAGGGUCGUGGGCAGCCUUGAGAAGACAAGGAAGCUCGUGCUCAGGCCUGCCCUGGCAGUGGGAGUGACUGCUGUGCUCAGCGUGGCCGGGAUUCUGAAUGCCGCGCAGCCCCCGGCUGUGAAAACUGUGGAGGUGCCCAUCCAUCAGCUGCCUGCCUCAAUGAACAACCUCAAGAUCGUGCUCCUCUCAGACAUUCACUUGGGCCCCACAGUGGGCAGGACCAAGAUGGAAAUGUUUGUGAGGAUGGUGAAUGUGCUGGAACCAGACAUCACGGUGAUUGUGGGUGACCUCUCCGACUCAGAAGCCUCGGUCCUGCGGACGGCUGUCGCUCCUCUGGGCCAGCUUCAUUCACAUCUCGGUGCCUACUUCGUCACAGGCAAUCAUGAGUACUACACGUCAGAUGUCAGCAACUGGUUUGCACUUCUGGAAUCCCUGCAUGUCCAGCCUCUUCAUAAUGAGAACGUGAAGAUUUCCGCCACACGGGCCCAACGUGGUGGUGGUGGCAGUGGCAGUGGGAGUGAGGAUGAGGACUGGAUCUGCUUGGCUGGGGUGGACGAUAUUGAAGCAGACAUCCUGCACUACUCUGGCCAUGGCAUGGAUCUUGACAAGGCCCUGGAGGGCUGCAGCCCAGACCACACAAUCAUCUUGCUAGCUCACCAGCCCCUGGCUGCCAAGAGAGCUCUCCAGGCUCGGCCAGAUAUUAACCUGAUCCUUUCUGGGCACACACAUGCUGGGCAGAUCUUCCCCUUGAACGUAGCAGCCUAUCUCCUGAAUCCCUUCUUUGCUGGUCUCUACCAGGUGGCCCAGGCUACAUUCGUGUAUGUCAGCCCAGGCACAGCCUACUACGGGAUACCCAUGAGGCUGGGUAGCAGGGCCGAGAUCACAGAGCUCAUCCUGCAGCGGUCUCCCUGAACUGGCCCUGCCCUGUGCACCUCUGCCCUGCCCUUGUCCUCGACCCUCCAUCCUGCUUCAGAGUGGUUUGCCUGCUUUUCCCCUCCAGCCUUGCCCACUCAUCCUUGCCUACACACCCUUGGUCACAAGCCUGACUCAAACAGUGACUUAUGGUGGGCCUGCCUGGCAUGUUCAGGCUGGUUUAACUAUUUCCUUGGCCAGUUGCUUUUUUUGAUGCACUUGUGAGAUCACUAAGGUCACAUAUAUUAGCACUCCCCUCUAUUUUCCAGAUGAUGUGGAAUGGGGACCUUCUCCUGCAGAGCUCCCAGGGAUGAACCUCCCCUCGGGGUUGCUAGAAAGGCAUACCUCUAGAAGGUGGGGCGGGGAGGAGCAGGAGCAUUUUUCUCCUGGUGUUUUAAAAUUGUCUUUAGGACUUAAGUGGUUUCCAGAAUCAUUGAUCCAGAGCCUUUCUGGGGAAGGGGUAGUGUUGCCAGGUAAUUUGGGAGAACAGGCAAGAUGGAAGGGCCCUCUGGCUGCUAGAGAAGAAUAUUUUCUUUUCCUCUGAUUCUAUCAGGAUCACCUCUAUUGAGGGCAUCAGCAAAAUCUACUGGAAUGCAAAGCUCCUCCUGUUCCAGGCCUUGAGGGAUGCUAUUUAACUGUCUGUGCUCCUGGGCCUUUGGGGGCAAGGUCAGGGGAGAAGAACGGUGGGCGCCAUGGUCGGUGAUGGUGAGAACAUGGCUGCUUAGGAAUUCAGAGGGCUUUGCCUCCCUUGUCUCAUUUUAUACAACCCUUCGGGGAGCUCACUGGGGACAGGCUGCUUUUCCCUAUUUGGAGAUAAGGAAACCAAGGCAAAGAGAGAUAGGGCACAGGCAGUAUGACAAGAUAUGUAGGAGAUUUGGGGCUAGAAACCAGGUCUUGUACCUCCCAGUAAAAGCGGUGCUUUUGCCCUUUUGCCAGAAGCAAUAGAUCCUUUGAUCCUGAGAUGGAGAUAAGCACCCGUGUUAGAAAAGGCCUCACUGAGAAGACAGGGCUGGGCUGGUUUCCUGCUGGGUGAUUUAGGCUUGUGAUGGAAAGUCUUCCUCCAAUGGGGAGUGAAGACACUCGCUCUGACUGGAGAGGCUAACCCUGCUGCUCACUCAUAGGGCAGCGUUGGGUGGGUGACUUUCCCUCACUCAGCCUUGGUUUCCAUCAACCCUAAAAUGGGGAUAAUUAUCGUAUCUACCUCAAGAUUGUUUUGUCAGGAGGGAUCCAUCAAGCCUUGUGCAUGAGUUCCACAUGGCACAGCGUGCACAGUAAACACUCAAUGUUAAUUUUUCAACGUUCCAGUGGAGCUUGCUAAGGAACUCUGUUGGGCACAGGUGCCCAGAGGAUUCAUGGAGCAGCCAGUCCUGGGGAAUGUGAGUGGGUAGCGAGCUGCCUGCUGCUGGGGCAGGUGAUGUGUCAAAGCAGCAACUGCUAGGGGUUUGCCUUCCUUCCCUCAUGUGCAUUCUGGCAGGCAAAGGGGGUUUCUUCCUUUCCUCCUUGUCCUCCUGGUGUAUAGUGGGGUUCUGGGGGAUCUGGAGACCACCCUUUUUGUUCCCAGGCAGCCACGGUAUUGACAGUGGGCCAUACCAUGCAGUUUAAAAUGUAUCUUUGAGUUGAAAUUUUGGUGGUUUCCUUAUUCUUUUUUCUCUCUUCACUGUCCUUCCAAACUCACUUUUCUUGUGUCCCGACCGCAUUUUGUGAAUCAUCCUUACUCCCUUUAAGUUCUCGCUUUGGAUUUCACCAGGUGGGCUAGAUGGUGCCAUUUCACUUCCACUGUUUGAUGCGGCUGGUAAUGUUUGACUCACCUGUUACGUGUUAUUUCACUGGUUUCUUGAUUUUACAUCUUUCUCAUCAGUGACCUGGGCUUGAUGAAAUUAGCUUUCAUUAAGUCCUAUUUUUUUUUUAAUUUUGCAUCCUUACCUCUUUUCUUUCUCUUGAAUGCCAUCAUUGUGUGGUCUUAUGUACCCUUCAUCCACUCUGAAGUCCUUGCUUGACUGAUUGCUUUCUAUUAGCAGAAAGAAAACAGGUCCAUCCUAUGUAUCUGAGAAACAACAUCAACACCCUCUCGUAUGUGGUUUGUAUUCCCUGACGCGGCGGACAUUUUUGCAGCAGAAAUUUCUCCAUCACUGUCCAGAUUCUGGCCCUGGUGGGCAGGUCUCCAUGACACCUUUAGUCCCUUUGUUCAACAUUCUUAAACCAUGGACCUUUUUGUUUGUUUGUGGCCGGGGGAGGUGGUGAGAAACGUUACUUGAAGCUUGAUCAUUCUUUCAAUUUCAUUUGUUUCUUUAUUUUUAAUCUGUUAGAUGCAAAUUGAAAUGCAAUGCUUUUUGAAAAUCAGCAAUAGUGUCUGUAGUAUAUGAUGCUGUCACAAAAUCUCAAUAAAUUGAUCCUGCUGCCAUUCCUUCCAAA